AUUUCUUGGUCCCUCCUGAUGAGAGAAGAUGGGCAGCCAGGGGCCCGUUCCCCGGGAGAUGCUGGUGAUCUGGAUUCUGACGCUGGCUCUCCGGCUCUGCGCGUCCGUUACUACAGUGACACCAGGCUCAACAGUAAACACCAGUAUUGGAGGUAAUACAACUUCUGCAUCCACACCCAGUUCAAGCGACCCUUUUACCACCUUUAGUGACUAUGGGGUGUCAGUCACAUUUAUCACGGGCUCAACUGCAACAAAACACUUCCUUGACAGCUCCACAAACUCAGGCCACAGUGAGGAAUCAACAGUAUCCCACAGCGGCCCAGGUGCAACUGGAACAACACUCUUCCCUUCCCACUCUGCAACCUCAGUUUUUGUUGGAGAACCUAAAACCUCACCCAUCACUUCAGCCUCAAUGGAAACAACAGCGUUACCUGGCAGUACCACAACAGCAGGCCUGAGUGAGAAAUCUACCACCUUCUACAGUAGCCCCAGAUCACCAGACAGAACACUCUCACCUGCCCGCACGACAAGCUCAGGCGUCAGUGAAAAAUCAACCACCUCCCACAGCCGACCAGGCCCAACGCACACAAUAGCGUUCCCUGACAGUACCACCAUGCCAGGCGUCAGUCAGGAAUCUACAGCUUCCCACAGCAUCCCCGGCUCCACAGACACAACACUGUCCCCUGGCACUACCACACCAUCAUCCCUUGGUCCAGAAUCUACUACCUUCCACAGCAGCCCAGGCUACACUAAAACAACACGCUUACCUGACAACACCACAACCUCAGGCCUCCUUGAAGCAUCUACGCCCGUCCACAGCAGCACUGGAUCGCCACACACAACACUGUCCCCUUCCAGCUCUACAACCCAUGAGGGAGAACCUACCACCUUCCAGAGCUGGCCAAGCUCAAAGGACACUUCGCCUGCACCUUCUGGUACCACAUCAGCCUUUGUUAAACUAUCUACAACUUAUCACAGCAGCCCGAGCUCAACUCCAACAACCCACUUUUCUGCCAGCUCCACAACCUUGGGCCAUAGUGAGGAAUCGACACCAGUCCACAGCAGCCCAGUUGCAACUGCAACAACACCCCCACCUGCCCGCUCCGCGACCUCAGGCCAUGUUGAAGAAUCUACAGCCUACCACAGGAGCCCGGGCUCAACUCAAACAAUGCACUUCCCUGAAAGCUCCACAACUUCAGGCCAUAGUGAAGAAUCAGCAACUUUCCACGGCAGCACAACACACACAAAAUCUUCAACUCCUAGCACCACAGCUGCCCUAGCACAUACAAGCUACCACAGCAGCCUGGGCUCAACUGAAACAACACACUUCCGUGAUAGCUCCACAAUCUCAGGCCGUAGUGAGGAAUCAAAAGCAUCCCACAGCAGCCCAGAUGCAAUGGCAACAACAGUCUUACCUGCCGGCUCUACACCCUCAGUUCUUGUUGGAGACUCGACGCCCUCACCCAUCAGUUCAGGCUCAAUGGAAACCACAGCGUUACCCGGCAGUACCACAAAACCAGGCCUCAGUGAGAAAUCUACCACUUUCUACAGUAGCCCCAGAUCACCAGACACAACACACUUACCUGCCAGCAUGACAAGCUCAGGCGUCAGUGAAGAAUCCACCACCUCCCACAGCCGACCAGGCUCAACACACACAACAGCAUUCCCUGGCAGUACCACCAUGCCAGGCCUCAGUCAGGAAUCUACAGCUUCCCACAGCAGCCCAGGCCCCACAGACACAACAUUGUCCCCUGGCAGUACCACAGCAUCAUCCCUUGGUCCAGAAUAUACUACCUUCCACAGCCGCCCAGGCUCCACUGAAACAACACUCUUACCUGACAACACCACAGCCUCAGGACUCCUUGAAGCAUCUAUGCCCGUCCACAGCAGCACCAGAUCGCCACACACAACACUGUCCCCUGCCGGCUCUACAACCCGUCAGGGAGAAUCUACCACAUUCCAUAGCUGGCCAAGCUCAAAGGACACUAGGCCUGCACCUCCUACUACCACAUCAGCCUUUGUUGAGCCAUCUACAACCUCCCACGGCAGCCCGAGCUCAAUUCCAACAACCCACAUUUCUGCCCGCUCCACAACCUCAGGCCUCGUUGAAGAAUCUACGACCUACCACAGCAGCCCGGGCUCAACUCAAACAAUGCACUUCCCUGAAAGCGACACAACUUCAGGCCGUGGUGAAGAAUCAACAACUUCCCACAGCAGCACAACACACACAAUAUCUUCAGCUCCUAGCACCACAUCUGCCCUUGUUGAAGAACCUACCAGCUACCACAGCAGCCCGGGCUCAACUGCAACAACACACUUCCCUGACAGCUCCACAACCUCAGGCCGUAGUGAGGAAUCAACAGCAUCGCACAGCAGCCAAGACGCAACGGGAACAAUAGUCCUACCUGCCCGCUCCACAACCUCAGUUCUUCUUGGAGAAUCUACGACCUCACCCAUCAGUUCAGGCUCAAUGGAAACGACAGCGUUACCCGGCAGUACCACAACGCCAGGCCUCAGUGAGAGAUCUACCACUUUCCAUAGUAGCCCCAGAUCACCAGCCACAACACUCUCACCUGCCAGCACGACAAGCUCAGGCGUCAGUGAAGAAUCCACCACCUCCCGCAGCCGACCAGGCUCAACGCACACAACAGCAUUCCCUGACAGCACCACCACGCCAGGCCUCAGUCGGCAUUCUACAACUUCCCACAGCAGCCCAGGCUCAACGGAUACAACACUGUUACCUGCCAGCACCACCACCUCAGGCCCCAGUCAGGAAUCAACAACUUCCCACAGCAGCUCAGGUUCAACUGACACAGCACUGUCCCCUGGCAGUACCACAGCCUUAUCCUUUGGUCAAGAAUCUACAACCUUCCACAGCAACCCAGGCUCCACUCACACAACACUCUUCCCUGACAGCACCACAAGCUCAGGCAUCGUUGAAGCAUCUACACGCGUCCACAGCAGCACUGGCUCACCACGCACAACACUGUCCCCUGCCAGCUCCACAAGCCCUGGACUUCAGGGAGAAUCUACUGCCUUCCAGACCCACCCAGCCUCAACUCACACAACGCCUUCACCUCCUAGCACCGCAACAGCCCCUGUUGAAGAAUCUACAACCUACCACCGCAGCCCAGGCUCGACUCCAACAACACACUUCCCUGCCAGCUCCACAACUUCGGGCCACAGUGAGAAAUCAACAAUAUUCCACAGCAGCCCAGAUGCAAGUGGAACAACACCCUCAUCUGCCCACUCCACAACCUCAGGUCGUGGAGAAUCUACAACCUCACGCAUCAGUCCAGGCUCAACUGAAAUAACAACGUUACCUGGCAGUACCACAACACCAGGCCUCAGUGAGGCAUCUACCACCUUCUACAGCAGCCCCAGAUCACCAACCACAACACUCUCACCUGCCAGCAUGACAAGCCUGGGCGUCGGUGAAGAAUCCACCACCUCCCGUAGCCAACCAGGUUCUACUCACUCAACAGUGUCACCUGCCAGCACCACCACGCCAGGCCUCAGUGAGGAAUCUACCACCGUCUACAGCAGCAGCCGAGGCUCAACUGAAACCACAGUGUUCCCUCACAGCACCACAACCUCAGUUCAUGGUGAAGAGCCUACAACCUUCCACAGCCGGCCAGCCUCAACUCACACAACACUGUUCACUGAGGACAGCACCACCUCGGGCCUCACUGAAGAAUCUACAGCCUUCCCCGGCAGCCCAGCCUCCACCCAAACAGGGUUACCUGCCACACUCACAACCGCAGACCUCGGUGAGGAAUCAACUACCUUUCCCAGCAGCUCAGGCUCAACUGGAACAAAACUCUCACCUGCCCGCUCCACCACCUCUGGCCUCGUUGGAGAAUCCACACCCUCACGCCUCAGUCCAAGCUCAACCGAAACAACAACUUUACCUGGCAGUCCCACAACACCAAGCCUCAGUGAGAAAUCAACCACCUUCUACACUAGCCCCAGAUCACCAGAUGCAACACUCUCACCUGCAACCACAACAAGCUCAGGCGUCAGCGAAGAAUCCAGCACAUCCCACAGUCAACCAGGCUCAACGCACACAACAGCAUUCCCUGACAGCACCACCACCUCAGACCUCAGUCAGGAACCUACAACUUCCCACAGCAGCCAAGGCUCAACAGAGGCAACACUGUCCCCUGGCAGUACCACAGCCUCAUCCCUUGGUCAACAAUCUACAACCUUCCACAGCAGCCCAGGCGACACUGAAACCACACUCUUACCUGACGACACCAUAACCUCAGGCCUCGUGGAGGCAUCUACACCCACCCACAGCAGCACUGGCUCGCUACACACAACACUGACCCCUGCCAGCUCCACAAGCGCUGGCCUUCAGGAAGAAUCUACCACUUUCCAGAGCUGGCCAAGCUCAAGUGACACAACACCUUCACCUCCCGGCACCACAGCAGCCCCUGUUGAAGUAUCCACAACCUACCACAGCCGCCCGAGCUCAACUCCAACAACACACUUUUCUGCCAGUUCCACAACCUUGGGCCGUAGUGAGGAAUCAACAACAGUCCACAGCAGCCCAGGUGCAACUGGAACAGCACUCUUCCCUACCCGCUCUGCAACCUCAGUUCUUGUUGGAGAACCUACAACGUCACCCAUCAGUUCAGGCUCAACGGAAACAACAGCGUUACCUGGCAGUACCACAACAGCAGGCCUGAGUGAGAAAUCUACCACCUUCUACAGUAGCCCCAGAUCACCGGACACAACACUCUCACCUGCCAGCACGACAAGCUCAGGCGUCAGUGAAGAAUCCACCACCUCCCACAGCCGACCAGGCUCAACGCACACAACAGCAUUCCCUGGCAGUACCACCAUGCCAGGCGUCAGUCAGGAAUCUACAGCUUCCCACAGCAGCCCAGGCUCCACAGACACAACAUUGUCCCCUGGCAGUACCACAGCAUCAUCCCUUGGUCCAGAAUCUACUACUUUCCACAGCAGCCCAGGCUCCACUGAAACAACACUCUUACCUGACAACACCACAGCCUCAGGCCUCCUUGAAGCAUCUACGCCCGUCCACAGCAGCACUGGAUCGCCACACACAACACUGUCCCCUGCCGGCUCUACAACACGUCAGGGAGAAUCUACCACCUUCCAGAGCUGGCCAAGCUCAAAGGACACUAUGCCUGCACCUCCUACUACCACAUCAGCCUUUGUUGAGCUAUCUACAACCUCCCACGGCAGCCCGAGCUCAACUCCAACAACCCACUUUUCUGCCAGCUCCACAACCUUGGGCCGUAGUGAGGAAUCGACAACAGUCCACAGCAGCCCAGUUGCAACUGCAACAACACCCUCGCCUGCCCGCUCCACAACCUCAGGCCUCGUUGAAGAAUCUACGGCGUACCACAGCAGCCCGGGCUCAACUCAAACAAUGCACUUCCCUGAAAGCUCCACAGCUUCAGGUCGUAGUGAAGAAUCAAGAACUUCCCACAGCAGCACAACACACACAAUAUCUUCACCUCCUAGCACCACAUCUGCCCUUGUUGAAGAACCUACCAGCUACCACAGCAGCCCGGGCUCAACUGCAACAACACACUUCCCUGACAGCUCCACAACCUCAGGCCGUAGUGAGGAAUCAACAGCAUCCCACAGCAGCCAAGACGCAACGGGAACAAUAGUCCUACCUGCCCGCUCCACAACCUCAGUUCUUCUUGGAGAAUCUACGACCUCACCCAUCAGUUCAGGCUCAAUGGAAACGACAGCGUUACCCGGCAGUACCACAACGCCAGGCCUCAGUGAGAAAUCUACCACUUUCCACAGUAGCCCCAGAUCACCAGCCACAACACUCUCACCUGCCAGCACGACAAGCUCAGGCGUCAGUGAAGAAUCCACCACCUCCCACAGCCGACCAGGCUCAACGCACACAACAGCAUUCCCUGACAGCACCACCACGCCAGGCCUCAGUCGGCAUUCUACAACUUCCCACAGCAGCCCAGGCUCAACGGAUACAACACUGUUACCUGCCAGCACCACCACCUCAGGCCCCAGUCAGGAAUCAACAACUUCCCACAGCAGCCCAGGUUCAACUGACACAGCACUGUCCCCUGGCAGUACCACAGCCUUAUCCUUUGGUCAAGAAUCUACAACCUUCCACAGCAGCCCAGGCUCCACUCACACAACGCUCUUCCCUGACAGCACCACAAGCUCAGGCAUCGUUGAAGCAUCUACACGCGUCCACAGCAGCACUGGCUCACCACGCACAACACUGUCCCCUGCCAGCUCCACAAGCCCUGGACUUCAGGGAGAAUCUACCGCCUUCCAGACCCACCCAGCCUCAACUCACACGACGCCUUCACCUCCUAGCACCGCAACAGCCCCUGUUGAAGAAUCUACAACCUACCACCGCAGCCCAGGCUCGACUCCAACAACACACUUCCCUGCCAGCUCCACAACUUCGGGCCACAGUGAGAAAUCAACAAUAUUCCACAGCAGCCCAGAUGCAAGUGGAACAACACCCUCAUCUGCCCACUCCACAACCUCAGGUCGUGGAGAAUCUACAACCUCACGCAUCAGUCCAGGCUCAACUGAAAUAACAACGUUACCUGGCAGUACCACAACACCAGGCCUCAGUGAGGCAUCUACCACCUUCUACAGCAGCCCCAGAUCACCAACCACAACACUCUCACCUGCCAGUAUGACAAGCCUAGGCGUCGGUGAAGAAUCCACCACCUCCCGUAGCCAACCAGGUUCUACUCACUCAACAGUGUCACCUGCCAGCACCACCACGCCAGGCCUCAGUGAGGAAUCUACCACCGUCUACAGCAGCAGCCCAGGCUCAACUGAAACCACAGUGUUCCCUCGCACCCCCACAACCUCAGUUCGUGGUGAAGAGCCUACAACCUUCCACAGCCGGCCAGCCUCAACUCACACAACACUGUUCACUGAGGACAGCACCACCUCGGGCCUCACUGAAGAAUCUACAGCCUUCCCCGGCAGCCCAGCCUCCACCCAAACAGGGUUACCUGCCACACUCACAACCGCAGACCUCGGUGAGGAAUCAACUACCUUUCCCAGCAGCUCAGGCUCAACUGGAACAACACUCUCACCUGCCCGCUCCACCACCUCUGGCCUCGUUGGAGAAUCCACACCCUCACGCCUCAGUCCAAGCUCAACCGAAACAACAACUUUACCCGGCAGUCCCACAACACCAAGCCUCAGUGAGAAAUCAACCACCUUCUACACUAGCCCCAGAUCACCAGAUGCAACACUCUCACCUGCAACCACAACAAGCUCAGGCGUCAGUGAAGAAUCCAGCACAUCCCACAGUCAACCAGGCUCAACGCACACAACAGCAUUCCCUGACAGCACCACCACGCCAGGCCUCAGUCGGCAUUCUACAACUUCCCACAGCAGCCCAGGCUCAACGGAUACAACACUGUUACCUGCCAGCACCACCACCUCAGGCCCCAGUCAGGAAUCAACAACUUCCCACAGCAGCCCAGGUUCAACUGACACAGCACUGUCCCCUGGCAGUACCACAGCCUUAUCCUUUGGUCAAGAAUCUACAACCUUCCACAGCAGCCCAGGCUCCACUCACACAACACUCUUCCCUGACAGCACCACAAGCUCAGGCAUCGUUGAAGCAUCUACACGCGUCCACAGCAGCACUGGCUCACCACGCACAACACUGUCCCCUGCCAGCUCCACAAGCCCUGGACUUCAGGGAGAAUCUACCACCUUCCAGACCCACCCAGCCUCAACUCACACGACGCCUUCACCUCCUAGCACCGCAACAGCCCCUGUUGAAGAAUCUACAACCUACCACCGCAGCCCAGGCUCGACUCCAACAACACACUUCCCUGCCAGCUCCACAACUUCGGGCCACAGUGAGAAAUCAACAAUAUUCCACAGCAGCCCAGAUGCAAGUGGAACAACACCCUCAUCUGCCCACUCCACAACCUCAGGUCGUGGAGAAUCUACAACCUCACGCAUCAGUCCAGGCUCAACUGAAAUAACAACGUUACCUGGCAGUACCACAACACCAGGCCUCAGUGAGGCAUCUACCACCUUCUACAGCAGCCCCAGAUCACCAACCACAACACUCUCACCUGCCAGUAUGACAAGCCUAGGCGUCGGUGAAGAAUCCACCACCUCCCGUAGCCAACCAGGUUCUACUCACUCAACAGUGUCACCUGCCAGCACCACCACGCCAGGCCUCAGUGAGGAAUCUACCACCGUCUACAGCAGCAGCCCAGGCUCAACUGAAACCACAGUGUUCCCUCGCAGCACCACAACCUCAGUUCGUGGUGAAGAGCCUACAACCUUCCACAGCCGGCCAGCCUCAACUCACACAACACUGUUCACUGAGGACAGCACCACCUCGGGCCUCACUGAAGAAUCUACAGCCUUCCCCGGCAGCCCAGCCUCCACCCAAACAGGGUUACCUGCCACACUCACAACCGCAGACCUCGGUGAGGAAUCAACUACCUUUCCCAGCAGCUCAGGCUCAACUGGAACAACACUCUCACCUGCCCGCUCCACCACCUCUGGCCUCGUUGGAGAAUCCACACCCUCACGCCUCAGUCCAAGCUCAACCGAAACAACAACUUUACCCGGCAGUCCCACAACACCAAGCCUCAGUGAGAAAUCAACCACCUUCUACACUAGCCCCAGAUCACCAGAUGCAACACUCUCACCUGCAACCACAACAAGCUCAGGCGUCAGUGAAGAAUCCAGCACAUCCCACAGUCAACCAGGCUCAACGCACACAACAGCGUUCCCUGACAGCACCACCACCUCAGGCCUCAGUCAGGAACCUACAGCUUCCCACAGCAGCCAAGGCUCAACAGAGGCAACACUGUCCCCUGGCAGUACCACAGCCUCAUCCCUUGGUCAACAAUCUACAACCUUCCACAGCAGCCCAGGCGACACUGAAACCACACUCUUACCUGACGACACCAUAACCUCAGGCCUCGUGGAGGCAUCUACACCCACCCACAGCAGCACUGGCUCGCUACACACAACACUGACCCCUGCCAGCUCCACAAGCGCUGGCCUUCAGGAAGAAUCUACCACUUUCCAGAGCUGGCCAAGCUCAAGUGACACAACACCUUCACCUCCCGGCACCACAGCAGCCCCUGUUGAAGUAUCCACAACCUACCACAGCCGCCCGAGCUCAACUCCAACAACACACUUUUCUGCCAGUUCCACAACCUUGGGCCGUAGUGAGGAAUCAACAACAGUCCACAGCAGCCCAGGUGCAACUGGAACAGCACUCUUCCCUACCCGCUCUGCAACCUCAGUUCUUGUUGGAGAACCUACAACGUCACCCAUCAGUUCAGGCUCAACGGAAACAACAGCGUUACCUGGCAGUACCACAACAGCAGGCCUGAGUGAGAAAUCUACCACCUUCUACAGUAGCCCCAGAUCACCGGACACAACACUCUCACCUGCCAGCACGACAAGCUCAGGCGUCAGUGAAGAAUCCACCACCUCCCACAGCCGACCAGGCUCAACGCACACAACAGCAUUCCCUGGCAGUACCACCAUGCCAGGCGUCAGUCAGGAAUCUACAGCUUCCCACAGCAGCCCAGGCUCCACAGACACAACACUGUCCCCUGGCAGUACCACAGCAUCAUCCCUUGGUCCAGAAUCUACUACCUUCCACAGCGGCCCAGGCUCCACUGAAACAACACUCUUACCUGACAACACCACAGCCUCAGGCCUCCUUGAAGCAUCUACGCCCGUCCACAGCAGCACUGGAUCGCCACACACAACACUGUCCCCUGCCGGCUCUACAACCCGUCAGGGAGAAUCUACCACCUUCCAGAGCUGGCCUAACUCGAAGGACACUACCCCUGCACCUCCUACUACCACAUCAGCCUUUGUUGAGCUAUCUACAACCUCCCACGGCAGCCCGAGCUCAACUCCAACAACCCACUUUUCUGCCAGCUCCACAACCUUGGGCCGUAGUGAGGAAUCGACAACAGUCCACAGCAGCCCAGUUGCAACUGCAACAACACCCUCGCCUGCCCGCUCCACAACCUCAGGCCUCGUUGAAGAAUCUACGACCUACCACAGCAGCCCGGGCUCAACUCAAACAAUGCACUUCCCUGAAAGCGACACAACUUCAGGCCGUGGUGAAGAAUCAACAACUUCCCACAGCAGCACAACACACACAAUAUCUUCAGCUCCUAGCACCACAUCUGCCCUUGUUGAAGAACCUACCAGCUACCACAGCAGCCCGGGCUCAACUGCAACAACACACUUCCCUGACAGCUCCACAACCUCAGGCCGUAGUGAGGAAUCAACAGCAUCCCACAGCAGCCAAGACGCAACGGGAACAAUAGUCCUACCUGCCCGCUCCACAACCUCAGUUCUUCUUGGAGAAUCUACGACCUCACCCAUCAGUUCAGGCUCAAUGGAAACGACAGCGUUACCCGGCAGUACCACAACGCCAGGCCUCAGUGAGAAAUCUACCACUUUCCACAGUAGCCCCAGAUCACCAGCCACAACACUCUCACCUGCCAGCACGACAAGCUCAGGCGUCAGUGAAGAAUCCACCACCUCCCACAGCCGACCAGGCUCAACGCACACAACAGCAUUCCCUGACAGCACCACCACGCCAGGCCUCAGUCGGCAUUCUACAACUUCCCACAGCAGCCCAGGCUCAACGGAUACAACACUGUUACCUGCCAGCACCACCACCUCAGGCUCCAGUCAGGAAUCAACAACUUCCCACAGCAGCUCAGGUUCAACUGACACAGCACUGUCCCCUGGCAGUACCACAGCCUUAUCCUUUGGUCAAGAAUCUACAACCUUCCACAGCAGCCCAGGCUCCACUCACACAACACUCUUCCCUGACAGCACCACAAGCUCAGGCAUCGUUGAAGCAUCUACACGCGUCCACAGCAGCACUGGCUCACCACGCACAACACUGUCCCCUGCCAGCUCCACAAGCCCUGGACUUCAGGGAGAAUCUACCGCCUUCCAGACCCACCCAGCCUCAACUCACACGACGCCUUCACCUCCUAGCACCGCAACAGCCCCUGUUGAAGAAUCUACAACCUACCACCGCAGCCCAGGCUCGACUCCAACAACACACUUCCCUGCCAGCUCCACAACUUCGGGCCACAGUGAGAAAUCAACAAUAUUCCACAGCAGCCCAGAUGCAAGUGGAACAACACCCUCAUCUGCCCACUCCACAACCUCAGGUCGUGGAGAAUCUACAACCUCACGCAUCAGUCCAGGCUCAACUGAAAUAACAACGUUACCUGGCAGUACCACAACACCAGGCCUCAGUGAGGCAUCUACCACCUUCUACAGCAGCCCCAGAUCACCAACCACAACACUCUCACCUGCCAGUAUGACAAGCCUAGGCGUCGGUGAAGAAUCCACCACCUCCCGUAGCCAACCAGGUUCUACUCACUCAACAGUGUCACCUGCCAGCACCACCACGCCAGGCCUCAGUGAGGAAUCUACCACCGUCUACAGCAGCAGCCCAGGCUCAACUGAAACCACAGUGUUCCCUCGCAGCACCACAACCUCAGUUCGUCGUGAAGAGCCUACAACCUUCCACAGCCGGCCAGCCUCAACUCACACAACACUGUUCACUGAGGACAGCACCACCUCGGGCCUCACUGAAGAAUCUACAGCCUUCCCCGGCAGCCCAGCCUCCACCCAAACAGGGUUACCUGCCACACUCACAACCGCAGACCUCGGUGAGGAAUCAACUACCUUUCCCAGCAGCUCAGGCUCAACUGGAACAAAACUCUCACCUGCCCGCUCCACCACCUCUGGCCUCGUUGGAGAAUCCACACCCUCACGCCUCAGUCCAAGCUCAACCGAAACAACAACUUUACCCGGCAGUCCCACAACACCAAGCCUCAGUGAGAAAUCAACCACCUUCUACACUAGCCCCAGAUCACCAGAUGCAACACUCUCACCUGCAACCACAACAAGCUCAGGCGUCAGCGAAGAAUCCAGCACAUCCCACAGUCAACCAGGCUCAACGCACACAACAGCGUUCCCUGACAGCACCACCACCUCAGGCCUCAGUCAGGAACCUACAACUUCCCACAGCAGCCAAGGCUCAACAGAGGCAACACUGUCCCCUGGCAGUACCACAGCCUCAUCCCUUGGUCAACAAUCUACAACCUUCCACAGCAGCCCAGGCGACACUGAAACCACACUCUUACCUGACGACACCAUAACCUCAGGCCUCGUGGAGGCAUCUACACCCACCCACAGCAGCACUGGCUCGCUACACACAACACUGACCCCUGCCAGCUCCACAAGCACUGGCCUUCAGGAAGAAUCUACCACUUUCCAGAGCUGGCCAAGCUCAAGUGACACAACACCUUCACCUCCCAGCACCACAGCAGUCCCUGUUGAAGUAUCCACAACCUACCACAGCCGCCCGAGCUCAACUCCAACAACACACUUUUCUGCCAGUUCCACAACCUUGGGCCGUAGUGAGGAAUCAACAACAGUCCACAGCAGCCCAGGUGCAACUGGAACAGCACUCUUCCCUACCCGCUCUGCAACCUCAGUUCUUGUUGGAGAACCUACAACGUCACCCAUCAGUUCAGGCUCAACGGAAACAACAGCGUUACCUGGCAGUACCACAACAGCAGGCCUGAGUGAGAAAUCUACCACCUUCUACAGUAGCCCCAGAUCACCGGACACAACACUUUCACCUGCCAGCACGACAAGCUCAGGCGUCAGUGAAGAAUCCACCACCUCCCACAGCCGACCAGGCUCAAUGCACACAACAGCAUUCCCUAGCAGUACCACCAUGCCAGGCGUCAGUCAGGAAUCUACAGCUUCCCACAGCAGCCCAGGCUCCACAGACACAACACUGUCCCCUGGCAGUACCACAGCAUCAUCCCUUGGUCCAGAAUCUACUACCUUCCACAGCAGCCCAGGCUCCACUGAAACAACACUCUUACCUGACAACACCACAGCCUCAGGCCUCCUUGAAGCAUCUACACCCGUCCACAGCAGCACUGGAUCGCCACACACAACACUGUCCCCUGCCGGCUCUACAACCCGUCAGGGAGAAUCUACCACCUUCCAGAGCUGGCCAAACUCGAAGGACACUACCCCUGCACCUCCUACUACCACAUCAGCCUUUGUUGAGCUAUCUACAACCUCCCACGGCAGCCCGAGCUCAACUCCAACAACCCACUUUUCUGCCAGCUCCACAACAUUGGGCCGUAGUGAGGAAUCGACAACAGUCCACAGCAGCCCAGUUGCAACUGCAACAACACCCUCGCCUGCCCGCUCCACAACCUCAGGCCUCGUUGAAGAAUCUACGACCUACCACAGCAGCCCGGGCUCAACUCAAACAAUGCACUUCCCUGAAAGCAACACAACUUCAGGCCGUGGUGAAGAAUCAACAACUUCCCACAGCAGCACAACACACACAAUAUCUUCAGCUCCUAGCACCACAUCUGCCCUUGUUGAAGAACCUACCAGCUACCACAGCAGCCCGGGCUCAACUGCAACAACACACUUCCCUGACAGCUCCACAACCUCAGGCCGUAGUGAGGAAUCAACAGCAUCCCACAGCAGCCAAGACGCAACGGGAACAAUAGUCCUACCUGCCCGCUCCACAACCUCAGUUCUUCUUGGAGAAUCUACGACCUCACCCAUCAGUUCAGGCUCAAUGGAAACGACAGCGUUACCCGGCAGUACCACAACGCCAGGCCUCAGUGAGAAAUCUACCACUUUCCACAGUAGCCCGAGCUCAACUCCAACAACCCACUUUUCUGCCAGCUCCACAACCUUGGGCCGUAGUGAGGAAUCGACAACAGUCCACAGCAGCCCAGUUGCAACUGCAACAACACCCUCGCCUGCCCGCUCCACAACCUCAGGCCUCGUUGAAGAAUCUACGGCGUACCACAGCAGCCCGGGCUCAACUCAAACAAUGCACUUCCCUGAAAGCUCCACAGCUUCAGGUCGUAGUGAAGAAUCAAGAACUUCCCACAGCAGCACAACACACACAAUAUCUUCACCUCCUAGCACCACAUCUGCCCUUGUUGAAGAACCUACCAGCUACCACAGCAGCCCGGGCUCAAUUGCAACAACACACUUUCCUGAGAGCUCCACAACCUCCGGCCGUAGUGAGGAAUCAACAGCAUCCCACAGCAGCCCAGAUACAAAUGGAAUCACACCCUUACCUGCCCAUUUUACUACCUCAGGCCGCAUUGCAGAAUCUACCACCUUCUAUAUCUCUCCAGGCUCAAUGGAAACAACAUUAGCCAGCACUGCCACAACACCAGGCCUCAGUGCAAAAUCUACCAUCCUUUACAGUAGCUCCAGAUCACCAGACCAAACACUCUCACCUGCCAGCAUGACAAGCUCCAGCAUCAGUGGAGAACCCACCAGCUUGUAUAGCCAAGCAGAGUCAACACACACAACAGCGUUCCCUGCCAGCACCACCACCUCAGGCCUCAGUCAGGAAUCAACAACUUUCCACAGUAAGCCAGGCUCAACUGAGACAACACUGUCCCCUGGCAGCAUCACAACUUCAUCUUUUGCUCAAGAAUUUACCACCCCUCAUAGCCAACCAGGCUCAGCUCUGUCAACAGUGUCACCUGCCAGCACCACAGUGCCAGGCCUUAGUGAGGAAUCUACCACCUUCUACAGCAGCCCAGGCUCAACUGAAACCACAGCGUUUUCUCACAGCAACACAAUGUCCAUUCAUAGUCAACAAUCUACACCCUUCCCUGACAGCCCAGGCUUCACUCACACAGUGUUACCUGCCACCCUCACAACCACAGACAUUGGUCAGGAAUCAACAGCCUUCCACAGCAGCUCAGACGCAACUGGAACAACACCCUUACCUGCCCGCUCCACAGCCUCAGACCUUGUUGGAGAACCUACAACUUUCUACAUCAGCCCAUCCCCUACUUACACAACACUCUUUCCUGCGAGUUCCAGCACAUCAGGCCUCACUGAGGAAUCUACCACCUUCCACACCAGUCCAAGCUUCACUUCUACAAUUGUGUCUACUGAAAGCCUGGAAACCUUAGCACCAGGGUUGUGCCAGGAAGGACAAAUUUGGAAUGGAAAACAAUGCGUCUGUCCCCAAGGCUACGUUGGUUACCAGUGCUUGUCCCCUCUGGAAUCCUUCCCUGUAGAAACCCCGGAAAAACUCAACGCCACUUUAGGUAUGACAGUGAAAGUGACUUACAGAAAUUUCACAGAAAAGAUGAAUGACGCAUCCUCCCAGGAAUACCAGAACUUCAGUACCCUCUUCAAGAAUCGGAUGGAUGUCGUUUUGAAGGGCGACAAUCUUCCUCAGUAUAGAGGGGUGAACAUUCGGAGAUUGCUCAACGGUAGCAUCGUGGUCAAGAACGAUGUCAUCCUGGAGGCAGACUACACUUUAGAGUAUGAGGAACUGUUUGAAAACCUGGCAGAGAUUGUAAAGGCCAAGAUUAUGAAUGAAACUAGAACAACUCUUCUUGAUCCUGAUUCCUGCAGAAAGGCCAUACUGUGCUAUAGUGAAGAGGACACUUUCGUGGAUUCAUCGGUGACUCCGGGCUUUGACUUCCAGGAGCAAUGCACCCAGAAGGCUGCCGAAGGAUAUACCCAGUUCUACUAUGUGGAUGUCUUGGAUGGGAAGCUGGCCUGUGUGAACAAGUGCACCAAAGGAACGAAGUCGCAAAUGAACUGUAACCUGGGCACAUGUCAGCUGCAACGCAGUGGCCCCCGCUGCCUGUGCCCAAAUACGAACACACACUGGUACUGGGGAGAGACCUGUGAAUUCAACAUCGCCAAGAGCCUCGUGUAUGGGAUCGUGGGGGCUGUGAUGGCGGUGCUGCUGCUCGCAUUGAUCAUCCUAAUCAUCUUAUUCAGCCUAUCCCAGAGAAAACGGCACAGGGAACAGUAUGAUGUGCCUCAAGAGUGGCGAAAGGAAGGCACCCCUGGCAUCUUCCAGAAGACGGCCAUCUGGGAAGACCAGAAUCUGAGGGAGAGCAGAUUCGGCCUUGAGAACGCCUACAACAACUUCCGGCCCACCCUGGAGACUGUUGACUCUGGCACAGAGCUCCACAUCCAGAGGCCGGAGAUGGUAGCAUCCACUGUGUGAGCCAACGGGGGCCUCCCACCCUCAUCUAGCUCUGUUCAGGAGAGCUGCAAACACAGAGCCCACCACAAGCCUCCGGGGCGGGUCAAGAGGAGACCGAAGUCAGGCCCUGAAGCCGGUCCUGCUCUGAGCUGACAGACUUGGCCAGUCCCCUGCCUGUGCUCCUGCUGGGGAAGGCUGGGGGCUGUAAGCCUCUCCAUCCGGGAGCUUCCAGACUCCCAGAAGCCUCGGCACCCCUGUCUCCUCCUGGGUGGCUCCCCACUCUGGAAUUUCCCUACCAAUAAAAGCAAAUCUGAAAGCUCA